CUGAGCGGCUCCGAGAAGACGCCCGGCCAGGGUGAACACCGCGGCAGGAGAAAACGGGAGACUGUGAAGAGCAUGGGGAGCCUUUGUCGUGCAGCGUGAAACCCUUGAGCCUUUGGCCUAGGAGCUGGGAGACUCAGGGGCCCUUCCCACACUCAGAAUUGGAGCAGGGCCUUCUAGACAGUCCCAGCACCAUGAGCCCUGAAAGGUCCCAAGAGGAGAGCCCAGAAGGAGACACAGAGAGAACAGAGCGGAAGCCCAUGGUGAGAAGUCGGGGAGGCGAAGCCAGACUCCCAGCAGGAGCUGAUCUCUGGAGUGCUGCAGACUCCUGGCCUGUACCCUUGGGUGACUCUGUCUGAAUGUGCAUGGAAUGGGGGCAGCUGGUCCUGGCCAGGACAUGGGGGAGAAAAGAACACUAGCAUCAGCGACUGCUCUGUGUCAGCAGAGAGCUAGGAAAAUGCUCAGUGUCUGCUCAGUUAAACAGGACACAAUCUGGAGAAGGAGGGAAGGUCUUUAUGUUUCACAGAGACUCCCAGAGGCCCCAGGCUAUGCCCUACACGCAGGGUAGAGGAAAAGGACCAGCUCGAUGUGUAUUAGUAAAUCACUGAUGGAAUCUGUUACUUCCUCUAGGUCAAAGAUGCCUUCAAAGACAUUUCCAUAUACUUCACCAAGGAAGAAUGGGCAGAAAUGGGAGACUGGGAGAAAACUCGCUAUAGGAAUGUGAAAAUGAACUAUAAUGCACUGAUUACUGUCUCAGAGCCACUCGACCAGCUUUCAUGUGUCACCGAAGGCAGGCCAUCAAACUCCAGGUGGAUGACACAGAAGAUUCCGAUGAAGAAUGGACACCUAGGCAGCAAGUCAAACCUCCUUGGAUGGCCUUCAGAGGAGAACAGAGUAAACACCAGAAGGGAAUGCCCAAGGCGUCAUUCAAUAAUGAAUCUAGUUUGAGAGAAUUGUCAGGAACGCCAAAUUUACUGAAUACAAGUGACUCAGAGCAGGCUCAGAAACCAGUGUCCCCUCCUGGAGAAGCAAGUACCUCUGGACAGCACUCUAGACUAAAACUGGAACUCAGGAGGAAGGAGACUGAAGGAAAGAUGUAUAGCCUGCGAGAAAGAAAGGGUCAUGCAUACAAAGAGAUCAGCGAGCCACAGGAUGAUGACUACCUCUAUUGUGAGAUGUGUCAGAACUUCUUCAUUGACAGCUGUGCUGCUCAUGGGCCCCCUACAUUUGUAAAGGACAGUGCAGUGGACAAGGGGCAUCCCAACCGUUCAGCCCUCAGUCUGCCCCCGGGGCUGAGAAUUGGGCCAUCAGGCAUCCCUCAGGCUGGGCUUGGAGUAUGGAACGAGGCAUCUGAUCUGCCACUGGGUCUGCACUUUGGCCCCUAUGAGGGCCGAAUUACAGAAGACGAAGAGGCAGCCAACAGUGGAUAUUCCUGGCUAAUCACCAAGGGGAGAAACUGCUAUGAGUAUGUGGAUGGAAAAGAUAAAUCCUCGGCCAACUGGAUGAGGUAUGUGAACUGUGCCCGGGAUGAUGAAGAGCAGAACCUGGUGGCCUUCCAGUACCACAGGCAGAUCUUCUAUAGAACCUGCCGAGUCAUUAGGCCAGGCUGUGAACUGCUGGUCUGGUCUGGGGAUGAGUAUGGCCAGGAACUGGGCAUCAGAUCUUCUAUAGAACCUGCCGAGUCAUUAGGCCAGGCUGUGAACUGCUGGUCUGGUAUGGGGAUGAGUAUGGCCAGGAACUGGGCAUCAAGUGGGGCAGCAAGUGGAAGAAAGAGCUCAUGGCAGGGAGAGAACCAAAGCCAGAGAUCCAUCCAUGUCCCUCAUGCUGUCUGGCCUUUUCAAGUCAAAAAUUUCUCAGUCAACAUGUGGAACGCAAUCACUCCUCUCAGAACUUCCCAGGACCAUCUGCAAGAAAACUUCUCCAACCAGAGAAUCCCUGCCCAGGGGAUCAGAAUCAGGAGCGGCAAUAUUCUGAUCCACGCUGCUGUAAUGACAAAACCAAAGGUCAAGAGAUCAAAGAAAGGUCCAAACUCUUGAAUAAAAGGACAUGGCAGAGGGAGAUUUCAAGGGCCUUUUCUAGCCCACCCAAAGGACAAAUGGGGAGCUCUAGAGUGGGAGAAAGAAUGAUGGAAGAAGAGUCCAGAACAGGCCAGAAAGUGAAUCCAGGGAACACAGGCAAAUUAUUUGUGGGGGUAGGAAUCUCAAGAAUUGCGAAAGUCAAAUAUGGAGAGUGUGGGCAAGGUUUCAGUGAUAAGUCAGAUGUUAUUACACACCAAAGGACACACACAGGGGGGAAGCCCUACGUCUGCAGAGAGUGUGGGAGGGCUUUAGCCGGAAGUCAGACCUCCUCAGUCACCAGAGGACACACACAGGGGAGAAGCCUUAUGUCUGCAGAGAGUGUGAGCGGGGCUUUAGCCGGAAGUCAGUCCUCCUCAUUCACCAGAGGACACACAGGGGAGACGCCCCAGUCUGCAGGAAGGAUGAGUAAGUCAUUAGUAAUAAAACCUUAUCUCAAUAGCCACAAGAAGACAAACGUGAUCACCACACACUUGCACACCCCAGCUCUGAGGUGGCUUCAGCGAAAGUCUGCUAACCCCUUACAUUCCCCGAGAGUGUAAAGAGAUCGGAAAUAACUAAUUAAACAAAUCCGCCACUUUCAUGACUAGAGUUGAGGAAGAACAGGGGAUAGUUCUGUAAGUGUUCGGGGGACGUCAACAUGUGUGGUUGUUUCCCGCACUGAUCCCCUCCAUUUUUUGUGUUUUGCCUCCUGUUCUAAUUAAUUUUGUCUCCAUACAUAUCUGAACCCCAAGUGUGUACCUCAUUCUUCCCUUAUCACUGAAGGAAGGAAGAGUCCAGAAGGGCCACAGAGAACUCAAACGUUCAGUUCAAGUCUCCACAGGAAUUCAACCCCAGAAAGACAUAAACUUGGAGUCCAUCUGGUUUAAUUAUUGGAGAAUCGAUUCCCAAGUCCAGGAAGAGAAAUGUAGGGUUUUACAGAGUCGCAGCAGGAAAGAGAGCUCCCUGGUCUCCUGGGAAGUGUGACCUCUUCUAAUGGACCCCUCUCCUCUGCUGCCAUACUCCCCCUUGGCUCCCCCUGUCUCCUCUCCUGAUUUCCUCCAAUCUCUGUAGCCCCAGAAGUGAACGCCAGACAGGAACACGCAUGUGUGUAUAUAUGUGUUCACGUGUGCUAUGUGUGUUAAGCCUGCAUGCAUGGGUGUGGGGGUAUGUGCCCUCUGUGUACGUAUCUGUGUGAGUGUGGGGGUUUCAAGGGUGUAUUAGGAAUAACGCUCAAAAUCCUAAGGAAAUUGAAUACUCUGAGAGAAGAGAGACAGACCCUCUCAUACUGUUUUAUAUUGUUUUAUACUCAGAAAAGGAAAAAGAAGCAAAACUAAAGGCAGGUAGCCUGGCGCCUAGGAACCAGACCUGAAACCAAGGAACCAGACCCGAAACCAGGCCUGGGCCGGCCUGACCUAAGCCUGGUAGUUAAAAUUCGACCCCUGACCUAGCAACUGAUGUUAUCUAUAGAUUAUAGAAAGACAUUGUGAAACUUCCCGGUCUGUUCUGUUCCACUCUGACCAUCGGUGCAUGCAGCCCCUGUCACCUACCCCCUGCUUGCUCAAUCGAUCACGACCCUCUCACGUGGACCCCCUUAGAGUUGUGAGCCCUUAAAAGGGACAGGAAUUGCUCACUCGGGGAGCUCGGCUCUUGAGACAGCAGUCUUGCUGAUGCUCCUGGCCGAAUAAACCGCUUCCUUCUUUAA